ACAAUUCUGCCUCUUCCAAAGGCUGCAGUUUAUCCAUCCUUAAAUCCUUGGAUGUGUUUAGACGCACAAGCAUUCAUCAACUAUUUGUUGAGCUCCUACUGUGUGCCAAGCACGCCUCUAAGCGCUGGGGACGGCGAUGGAACAAAACACACUUCCGGUUCUCUGGAGUUUACAUAUCGGCGUAAUUAUAGUGAACAUUAUUCACAACACUUCCGAUUACCAUCCAAAAGUUUUGCGAUUUUUGAAUGUGGCUUUUGAUGGCACAGGCGACUGCUUAAUUGCUGGGGACCACCAAGGAAAUAUUUAUGUUUUUGACUUACAUGGAAACAGGUUCAAUCUUGUUCAGCGAACAGCACAAGCUUGCACAGCUCUGGCCUUUAAUCUUCGUAGGAAAUCUGAAUUCCUUGUGGCAUUAGCUGAUUAUUCUAUUAAAUGUUUUGAUACAGUCACCAAGGAGCUAGUUAGCUGGAUGAGAGGACAUGAAUCAUCAGUAUUUUCGAUCUCUGUGCAUGCAUCAGGGAAAUAUGCCAUCACAACUUCUUCUGAUACAGCACAAUUAUGGGACUUGGAUACCUUUCAGAGAAAAAGAAAGCUGAAUAUUCGCCAGUCUGUGGGUAUACAGAAGGUUUUCUUUCUACCAUUAAGUAAUACCAUCCUCAGCUGUUUUAAAGAUAAUUCCAUUUUUGCCUGGGAAUGUGACACACUUUUUUGCAAAUAUCAAUUGCCAGCUCCACCUGAAAGCUCUAGUAUAUUAUACAAAGUGUUUGCUGUAACCAGAGAUGGCCGAAUCCUGGCUGCUGGAGGCAAGUCAAAUCAUCUUCAUUUGUGGUGCUUGGAAGCUAGGCAGCUCUUUAGAAUUAUCCAGAUGCCCACUAAAGUUCGAGCCAUUCGCCAUCUGGAAUUUCUUCCUGAUAGUUUUGAUGCUGGUUCUAAUCAGGUUCUUGGAGUACUAAGUCAAGAUGGUAUUAUGAGAUUUAUCAAUAUGCAGACUUGUAAACUUCUCUUUGAGAUUGGGAGCCUCGAUGAAGGAAUUAGCUCAUCAGCAAUUAGCCCACAUGGACGGUACAUUGCAUCUAUUAUGGAAAAUGGAAGUCUAAACAUAUAUUCAGUUCAGGCUUUAACACAAGAAAUAAAUAAGCCACCUCCGCCUUUAGUGAAAGUUAUUGAAGAUUUGCCCAAGAAUAAACUGAGUUCCAGUGAUCUUAAGAUGAAAGUAACAUCAGGGAGAGUACAGCAGCCAGCAAAAUCUAGGGAAAGCAAAAUGCAAACUAGAAUAUUAAAACAAGACCUGACUGGUGAUUUUGAAAGUAAAAAGAAUGAAUUACCAGAUGGAUUAAACAAAAAGCGUUUACAAAUCUUAUUAAAAGGCUAUGGUGAAUAUCCAACAAAAUACAGAAUGUUCAUUUGGCGCUCUCUGCUACAACUGCCUGAAAAUCAUACUGCGUUUAGUACCCUCAUAGAUAAGGGGACUCAUGUGGCAUUUCUCAACCUUCAGAAGAAAUACCCCAUCAAAAGUAGGAAGCUACUCAGAGUAUUACAGAGAACCUUAUCUGCAUUAGCUCACUGGUCUGUCAUUUUUAGUGACACACCAUAUCUUCCACUCUUGGCAUUUCCAUUUGUAAAAUUAUUCCAGAACAACCAACUCAUCUGUUUUGAAGUUAUUGCUACUCUCAUAAUCAAUUGGUGUCAACACUGGUUUGAAUAUUUUCCUAAUCCUCCUAUCAAUAUUCUUAGCAUGAUAGAAAAUGUUUUGGCAUUUCAUGACAAGGAACUGCUGCAACACUUCAUAGAUCAUGAUAUAACCUCCCAGCUAUAUGCAUGGCCUCUUCUUGAAACUGUGUUCUCAGAAGUGCUGACAAGAGAGGAGUGGCUGAAAUUGUUCGAUAAUAUCUUUUCCAACCAUCCUUCCUUCCUUCUGAUGACUGUUGUAGCCUACAACAUAUGUUCUAGAACGCCUCUGCUCAGCUGUAAUCUUAAAGAUGACUUUGAGUUUUUUUUUCACCAUCGGAAUAACCUGGAUAUAAAUGUUGUGAUUAGACAAGUUUAUCAUCUCAUGGAGACCACGCCUACUGACAUUCAUCCAGACAGCAUGCUUAAUGUUUUUGUUGCACUGACAAAAGGGCAGUAUCCAGUAUUUAAUCAAUAUCCAAAGUUUAUUGUGGACUAUCAAACACAGGAACGAGAAAGAAUAAGGAAUGAUGAAUUGGAUUACUUAAGAGAGAGGCAGACAGUUGAAGAUAUGCAAGCUAAAGUCGACCAGCAAAGAGUUGAAGAUGAAGCUUGGUACCAGAAACAGGAGCUGCUUCGUAAAGCUGAAGAAACAAGAAGAGAAAUGCUCUUACAAGAGGAGGAGAAAAUGAUACAACAAAGACAGAGGCUAGCUGCUGUGAAAAGAGAGCUGAAAGUAAAGGAAAUGCACUUACAAGAUGCUGCAAGAAGGCGUUUUCUGAAGCUUCAGCAAGAUCAACAGGAAAUGGAACUAAGAAGACUGGAUGAUGAAAUUGGGAGAAAGGUAUAUAUGAGAGAUCGAGAAAUUGCUGCCACAGCCAGAGACCUAGAAAUGAGACAGCUGGAACUCGAAUCACAAAAGAGACUUUAUGAGAAGAAUCUUACUGAAAAUCAAGAAGCUCUUGCAAAAGAAAUGCGAGCAGAUGCAGAUGCCUAUAGACGAAAAGUGGAUCUUGAAGAACACAUGUUUCAUAAGCUGAUAGAAGCAGGUGAAACCCAGAGCCAGAAAACUCAGAAGGUGAUUAAAGAAAAUUUGGCAAAGGCUGAACAAGCAUGCCUAAAUACCGACUGGCAGAUUCAGUCUUUACAUAAACAAAAAUGUGAUGAUCUACAACGAAACAAAUGUUACCAGGAAGUAGCCAAACUCCUUAGGGAAAACAGAAGGAAAGAAAUAGAGAUAAUAAAUGCAAUGGUGGAGGAGGAAGCCAAGAAGUGGAAGGAAGCUGAAGGAAAAGAGUUCCGUUUGAGAUCAGCAAAGAAAGCUUCUGCUCUUUCAGAUGCGUCUAGAAAGUGGUUUUUAAAGCAAGAGAUAAAUGCGGCUGUAGAACAUGCUGAAAAUCCAUGUCAUAAAGAAGAACCCAGGUUCCAAAAUGAACAGGACUCAAGCUGUUUGCCUAGAACCUCACAAUUAAAUGACUCUUCUGAAAUGGAUCCCUCAACACAGAUUUCUUUAAAUAGAAGAGCAGUAGAAUGGGACACCACGGGACAGAAUCUUAUUAAGAAAGUGAGAAAUCUUCGCCAGAGACUCACUGCCCGGGCUCGUCACAGAUGUCAAACCCCUCAUCUUUUGGCUGCAUAGAAUGCAUGUCACCUUGAGACGGUCGAGAGAGAGACCUAUUUUGCAAUCAGUGACAUUGAUUUUUAGAUUAUUUAUUUAAAAUUCCUAUAAAGAUCAGCCCUUUGUACAGAAAAAUGUGUCUAUAAAAAUUAUGUGUUAUUUAAUUCUGAUACUUUUUGGCUUGUAAAUGGCUUCUUGAACUUUUUACAAUAAAAAUGUUUUAGAAACUGUUAAA